CUUUUUGAGGAAGACGCGGUCGUAAGGGCUGAGGAUUUUUGGUCCGCACGCUCCUGCUCCUGACUCACCGCUGUUCGCUCUCGCCGAGGAACAAGUCGGUCAGGAAGCCCGCGCGCAACAGCCAUGGCUUUUAAGGAUACCGGAAAAACACCCGUGGAGCCGGAGGUGGCAAUUCACCGAAUUCGAAUCACCCUAACAAGCCGCAACGUAAAAUCCUUGGAAAAGGUGUGUGCUGACUUGAUAAGAGGCGCAAAAGAAAAGAAUCUCAAAGUGAAAGGACCAGUUCGAAUGCCUACCAAGACUUUGAGAAUCACUACAAGAAAAACUCCUUGUGGUGAAGGUUCUAAGACGUGGGAUCGUUUCCAGAUGAGAAUUCACAAGCGACUCAUUGACUUGCACAGUCCUUCUGAGAUUGUUAAGCAGAUUACUUCCAUCAGUAUUGAGCCAGGAGUUGAGUUGAUCGAAUCUACAGAUGCAGAACCCAUGGAUACAGAGGGCCAGCAGUACACUUUGAGAAGUGUAUUCGAAUCCCCGGGGACAUGUCCUUUUUAACUGCAUUCUCCUCCGCCAAAAAAGUGACCAAGCAGAGUCUUUCUCUGUCACCCAGGCUGGAGUGCAAUGGCGUGAUCUCAGCUCACUGCAACCUCUGCCUCCUGGGUUCAAGUGAUUCUCGUGUCUCAGCCUCCUGAGUAGCUGAGACUACAGGUGUGCACCAGUGUUCCCAGCUGAUUUUUGUAUUUUAUGUAGAGAUGGGGUUAUGCCAUUUUGGCCAGGCUAGUCUCGAACUCCUGAGCUCAGGUGAUACACACACCUCAGCAAAUCUUUUAAAUUAUACAUUCUGUGAUAUUUCCUUGACUUUCUUAUCCAGCACUUGUAUUGAUUAUUUUUCAUUUUGAUAAUGUUGGGUUUUUAAAAACUCCUUUAUGAUGGAAAAUUUCAAACAUACACAAAAGUAGAGAGAGAAUGGUAUAAUAAACCCACUCAGUUUUAAGGAUUGUCAACUAAUACCAGUUUUAUUUCAUGUAUGACUCCAACAACUUCCCCAACCAGCCUUCAGAUUAUUUGAAAGCAAAUUUCAGACAUCGUAUUUUACUCAUACAUUUUCUAGUAUCUAAAUCUGAAAGAGACUCUUUUCUAACAGUUCUGUAGCAUUAAUUAUACUCAUACUGUUGUGCAACAAAUAUCCAGAAAUCUUUUGUCUUGCGAAACUGAACCUCUUACCCAUUAAACACUAACUCCCUUUUUUUUCACCCUGAACCAUUGGCAACCACAAUUUUACUUUCUUUUUCUGUGAGUUUGAUUACUUGAUACUUCAUGUGAGUGGAAUCAUAUAAUAUUUGUCUUUUUGUGACUGACAUUUUAUUUAGCUUAAUGUCUUCAAGUUUGACCCAUACCAUAUCAUGUGGCAGGAUUUUUCCCUUUUUUUUUUUUUCAGACGGAGUCUCGCUCUGUCGCCCAGGCUGGAGUGCAGUGGCGCGAUCUCGGCUCACUGCAAGCUCCGCCUCCCGGGUUCAUGCCAUUCUCCUGCCUCAGCCUCCUGAGUAGCUGGGACUACAGGCGCCCACCACUAAACCCGGCUAAUUUUUUUGUAUUUUUAGUAGAGACAGAGUUUCACCAUGUUAAUGAGGAUGGUCUCCAUCUCCUGACCUCGUGAUUCGCUCGUCUCGGCCUCCCAAAGUGCUGGGAUUACAGGCGUGAGCCACCGCGCCCGGCCAUGAUUUUUCUUCUUUUUUAAGGCUGAAUAAUAUCUCAAUGUAUGUAUAUAUACCACUUUUUAAAAAUUCAUUCAUCUGUUGGACAUUUAGAUUGUUCCCACCUCUUGGCUAUUGUGAAUAAUGCUAUAAUAAACAUGAGUAUGCAAAUA